CGGCUCCCGCGGCUGCAGGCGCGCGGCUAGAGUGCCUGGCGGGCUCCGGCUUCCGCGUCCGCCCCGGCCCCGGUCCAGACUUAGUCUUCAGCUCCGCGCCCGCUCCGCCGCGGCCCACCGCGCCCGCCGGCAGCCGAGCCCCCAGCGACGCCCGCACAGCUCCGGGUGCCCAGACAGGGGGCCAUGCCGUGCCGGAGGGAGGAGGAAGAGGAAGCCGGCGAGGAGGCGGAGGGGGAGGAAGAGGAGGAGGACAGCUUCCUCCUACUGCAGCAGUCAGUGGCGCUGGGCAGCUCGGGCGAGGUGGACCGGCUGGUGGCCCAGAUCGGCGAGACGCUGCAGCUGGACGCGGCGCAGCACAGCCCGGCCUCGCCGUGCGGGCCCCCGGGGGCGCCGCUGCGGGCCCCGGGGCCCCUGGCUGCGGCGGUGCCGGCGGACAAGGCCAGGUCCCCGGCGGUGCCGCUGCUGCUGCCGCCCGCGUUGGCGGAGACUGUGGGCCCGGCGCCCCCUGGGGUCCUGCGCUGCGCCCUGGGGGACCGCGGCCGCGUGCGGGGCCGCGCUGCGCCCUACUGCGUGGCCGAGCUCGCCACAGGCCCCAGCGCGCUGUCCCCACUGCCCCCUCAGGCCGACCUUGAUGGGCCUCCGGGAGCUGGCAAGCAGGGCAUCCCGCAGCCGCUGUCGGGUCCGUGCCGGCGAGGAUGGCUCCGGGGCGCCGCCGCCUCCCGCCGCCUGCAGCAGCGACGCGGGUCCCAACCAGAAACCCGCACAGGCGACGACGACCCGCACCGGCUUCUGCAGCAGCUAGUGCUCUCUGGAAACCUCAUCAAGGAGGCCGUGCGAAGGCUUCAUUCGCGACGGCUGCAGUUACGUGCAAAGCUUCCCCAACGCCCGCUCCUGGGACCUCUGUCGGCCCCGGUGCAUGAACCCCCUUCGCCUCGCAGCCCUCGCGCGGCCUGCAGUGACCCUGGCGCCUCCGGGAGGGCGCAGCUCAGAACUGGCGACGGCGUUCUUGUGCCUGGCAGCUAACACGCCCGGGGUGGCCACAGCGCCAGCCUCAGACUGGAGGGCAAGGGGUUCCCUUGAGGGCUGCAGUUCUACUCAGGCUGGUGGAGAACUCUGGCUUUUGGAAGCGAGAGUAAAAAGCUAAUGACGAGGAACCGAAAAAUCGCGAGUGUUUCGCGGGUAACUGGGGUUGAGGGCCAAAAUAUUUGGAAUGAAGGACUUUGGCCCUAUUUAAGGCAGAUUUUACAGAGCGCACCUCAAACGUACAAGUCAGUAGGACUCCUUAUUUGGCGUGACCCGACCUGGCCGCGGAGCCUGCAUUUCCUCGCAGCCUCUCAGUGCCCUCCAGCCCCGCGACCAUGUGGCCACAAUCCACGCUUCUCCGGAUCGCGGUGCGCCGGAACCACGGAGGAUGAUGCCAGUUACUUGCUUUACCUUUUCAGGGCUGGCUCCUGAUCCACUUUGGGGGAGGAGAACAUGAGUAGAUAAUUUCAGGGUGCAGCCCAAUCUGCCAGACUUAAAAAAACCAUCUUGUGUCUUUGGAGGUGCUGCUUAAUACCAAACAUGCGGUGCCAUGAAGGGACCCUUUGGGGGUUGAAUAGGAGUUAACCCCUGCGCUCUCUUUGCAACUGUCUCUCUUCUCAGAGUGGUGGGGGAAGGCUGUACGACACGGGUGGGGAAAGGAGGUGGGGGCGGGGAGUAUUGAAUGGUGGUGGAAGGGUAGAGAGGCGCGGAGUGAACCCCACGCCCUGUCUAAAGUGUAUUUUCAGAGCCGGCCCGCCUCUCCUCGGUUCAAGGUCACUGUUUCCUGGGCACGCACUGGGUUGCGGGACAGAGUAGCCAGGUUCUGCCGGUGCUCGGAGAAGAGCGCAGUGUUUUGCAAGUGCUGGAGUCUCCUGAGGACACGCGCGUCGCCGCCACCGCGGGUGUGGGAAAGCGCGGACGUGCUGGGCGGCUGUGCUUCGGUAGGCGACCACCGCCCCUGGCCGCGCUCCGGGCUUUCACGGAAACUCCCGAGACCGGGCCCUGGGUUCCUCCUCUCCUACUCGGCUCUGCAGUCCUACUCAAGCGGGUGGCUCUGGGAUCCUGGGGGCCUGGGUUGGGGGCUAGGGAGACGCCAUGUGAUGGACACUCCAGGGACACACAGCCUAGCACAGCAGCUUAUAAUGGGCUCUCCGGGGCCAUUUGCAAUAACAGCUGCAAUUCCCUGGAUAGACGAGUUGAUUUCCUCCCUCUGCCCCUCCCCCAGCCAUGCCAGCUGGCCUUUGUAAGUGCAGGAAACCGAGUAGAAAAUGUGACCCUCCAAAUGGAGAAGCUGCAGGCUUUGCCAUUGUGAACCAUGGUGAAGUGCUUGGAACAUACUGUUCACUCACUCUAAAGGCGCUGAGACUGUGCUGUUGUUCUCGUUUUUAUAGUCAAUGGCUUGUUCAUCAUCCAGAUGUGGCUACUGACAUAUCUACACUUCGCACCGGAGUGUCUGGAAUUGUGGCUAUCCUGAUUAUAGGAUUUUAACUUAACUGAAAUGCCUGCUUUGAAUAAAUGUGUUGGGUUUUUUGUUUGGUUUUAUUUUAUACUUGCCAUCAGUGAAAAAGAUGUACAGAACACAUUUCUCUGAUCUCCAUAAACAUGAAAACACUUGAAAUCUC